AAACACACGGGCCGGGCGCACCCUGCAGCCGCGCCGCUCCGCGGCCUUCCGGCGCGGGGCCGGGGAACCUCCUCCCCAUCUGCGCACCCCCCGCCUUCGCGGCCCAGAUCCUCCCGCCAGCCCGGCCCCUCCUUCGCAGGGGGAGCGAGGCGACGGUUGCCGGGAAGCGCGCGCCACCUCUCCCUCCCAUUUUUCGUUCUCCCCUCGCGCGCCACCCGUUUUUCCUCUUUCUCCGUUAAUAACAGCUGGGUGGCUGGGGGAGGAGGGAAGGUGGCCCCGGCGGAGUCUGGGCGGGCGCCUCCCACUCAGCCGCCAGCCGCCGUGGGAGCCGGAGGAUGGCGGCGGUAGCAGCGGCCGCCCGAGAGGAGGCGGUGCCGAGAUCGGGGGCGCCGAGCGCGGCAGCAGAGAGCGGUAGCGGCCCGUCGUGGCGCACCAGAACCGAAACCAGCGGCAGCCGCACGGCCACUUGAGCCGCCCCUUCCUGCUGGAGCCAGCGAGGGGUGCCUGCAGCCGGGACCCCUUCCUCUCCGCGUCUCCUCGUCUCCCGCGCCCGCGUCAGGCCGUCGGCCUCGCCCGCCGCCCCAAGAAGAGCGCGCCGGGCGCCGACUGCCCCUCUGGACGCCGGGCGGCGGCCCUGGACGUGCGGGGGCCUCUCUGGGCCGGCCGCGGCGCCUGGGCCCUGCCCUCUAGCUCCCGCGCUCGCUCCCGCCCUCCCGGCUCUCGGGGCGCAGCGCGCGGGCCCGGCCCGGGGCAGGGCGGACAUGGGCGCCAAACAGAGCGGCCCGGCCGCCGCUAACGGCCGCACGCGCGCGUACUCGGGCUCGGAUCUACCUUCCAGUAGCAGCGGAGGCGCCAAUGGGACCGCGGGCGGCGGCGGGGGCGCUCGGGCCGCCGCCGCGGGGAGGUUCCCGGCUCAGGUGCCCAGCGCGCACCAGCCCAGCGCCUCCGGCGGCGCCGCGGCGGCCGCGGCGGCCCCGGCAGCCCCGGCGGCCCCGCGCAGCCGCUCCCUCGGCGGGGCCGUGGGGAGCGUGGCGUCGGGGGCCCGCGCGGCGCAGUCCCCCUUCAGCAUCCCGAACAGCAGCAGCGGCCCGUACGGCUCGCAGGACUCGGUGCACAGCAGCCCUGAGGACGGCGGCGGCGGCCGGGACCGGCCGGUGGGCGGGAGCCCCGGCGGGCCGCGCCUGGUGAUCGGCUCCUUACCAGCUCACCUCUCGCCGCACAUGUUUGGAGGAUUUAAGUGCCCUGUAUGCUCAAAAUUUGUAUCCUCAGAUGAAAUGGAUUUGCAUCUUGUAAUGUGUUUAACAAAGCCACGAAUAACCUAUAAUGAGGAUGUACUGAGUAAAGAUGCUGGGGAAUGUGCAAUAUGCCUUGAAGAAUUGCAGCAGGGAGAUACUAUAGCACGACUGCCUUGUCUAUGCAUAUAUCAUAAAGGCUGCAUAGAUGAAUGGUUUGAAGUAAAUAGAUCUUGCCCUGAGCACCCUUCAGAUUAAGCGUCAGCUUCCUGUUUUAUAGGUUUUCUUGUCUUGACAAGAUGCUUGAAAAACCAAGAGGAUAUGAAAAUCUGUCUCUGGAGAAACAAAGACGCAGGCAUACUCAGCCAGAAAUCUGAGUUUUGUGAGACUUGGUAAUACAGAGAUGGACAAUCGUACUGGGGUAAAAAAACCCUGCUGAAGAGAGGACAGUGACCACAGAACUCAGUGUACCAAACAUGCAUACAAAGGACACACAGGGAUUUUGAAAAUGCUGCACAUCCCUUAAUAGUCAUCUACAUAGGUAAUACUGAUAAACAUUUUGUAUUCAGACGCCAAAGUUAACUGAUUUAAAAGUUGAUUUACUUUUUAUUAAGUUCUCCAGAGCUGCACAACUAGUUAUGUUUUGAUUUGUUUUGUUUUUUAAUUUGGGGUCUCUUUGUUUUCCCCAACAUAAUGUUCAUAAUGUUUCUGCAUUCAUCUGUUCUUAAAUUGAAAAACAUAUAAUUUACUUCUUAUAAAUUGAAGUCUUAAAUGUGAAACCAAGAAAUGUAAUCAAGCAGUAAAAACAUCUGAAUGUAGACCAUGAUCUCAAGUUCUUCCAUUUUCUCCCCCACGAGUGGAAAAUAGACUUCUACAUAGGAAAGCUAAAAUAUGUUAAUAUUUUUAAAUUAAAGGUUUAAUAUCAGAAUGCAGUCCAAAGAGCAAAUCAUAUUACAUAAUUACAUUUUAAUUAAAUAUAGAAUAUUCUACUGAAUUGCAAUUUAUUAAAUAUUCUUAUCCUCUUAAAUAAAACUGCUCAACAGUUAAUCAGCAGUGAAUCAUCUUGCAGCUAUGCAAUUUAAAAAAAAUACAGAUUACCAAUUUCAAGUGCUGCCAGCUAAAAUAACUGUUUUAACGGGUAUCUUUUGUUUGUUCUUUUCACUUAAUUAUUUUAUUGUGCUUUGCAUCUCCAGGCAGUUCUCUCACAUUUGGGUAAAAUGUUUAGCAGGCUGUAAACUUAAGAAAAGGGUAAAAUAAAAUUUUCUGGAGAGGAACUUGGAAUUUGAGGGAGAUUUUAUAUACCUUUAAAAACUGUAAUUUAAUUGGGAUGCCAGGUUUAUAGCAAUUUGCAACUUUAAUUUUCCAGAUAAUCUGGAGGUUAGCAUUUGAUAAAUGAUUUUUUAAAGUAGAUAUGAAGAUUUUGUUAAUUUAUAAUUUAUUCAUGUGUUAUUACUGUAAUUGAAAAUGUUAUAGACACUUUUAAAUUCAGUUUGUGUAGAAAGAAAUGUGUUAAACAAAAUUAUGUUAAUAAAUAUUCCCACAUAAUACAUCUGAAUGGUUAAAAAUACUGGAAGAGUUGUCAGGGCUACAAUAGUGAAUGUCCUUUUUUUUAAUAUCAAAAAUAUCGAUAAGUAGGUUUUGUGUUUUCAACGUAGGGAAAAUGUUAUCAGUGAAUAGGUGGUGUACUUUACUUGGUAUAAUUUAAAGUUGCACAGUAAGUACUGUUUCCUUAUUUUAAUCUUUCUUUACUCAUAAUGUAUUUAAGAAUUUGCUGUUUUAUUUAACGCUGCUACUCUUAAUCUUCUCUAAAUUUUUCCCCCUACUUUCUUGCUUCUGUUUCACAUUUUUUAAAAGGGCAAGUACAGGAGCAACUGCUGCUACCCAGAAAAAUGUGUGUAUUAUAAAUAAUUAAAGAGUUUUUAAUUGCUUUCUGUA